GUGCACUCAAGAUUGUCCCCUGUCGAGUGUGGGCGAGGAGAGGCACACCACUAUUGUUUUAAUUUGCUUUUACCUGAUUCCUGGUAGGUUGAGCAUCUCUUCACAUUUAUCUCAGCUGCUUGGGUUUCCUCUGGGGCCUCUGAGAACCCUCAUCCAGGAGGGUCUCGGUCACACCAGGGUUGGUGUCACCUCCCUUCAGGGUGCCAGGCACCCCUCUUCAGAGGUGCUGAUUUCCUCAUCUGGCAUCCAGGCACAUUUCUGCGGCCGCCCUCCCAGGACAUGACACAGCUCAUUAGGUUUCAGCUUUUUAUCUUCCCUUUUAUGAGACUACACUGUAGUAACCUUUGCCGGACUUGGAUGUUCCCAGGCCUCCCAGUGUGUUCCCAGAGGGCAGACUUCUGCGUUAUGACCCGGCUGCUGGGCUACGUGGACCCCCUGGAUCCCAGCUUUGUGGCUGCCGUCAUCACCAUCACCUUCAAUCCGCUCUACUGGAAUGUGGUUGCACGAUGGGAACACAAGACCCGCAAGCUGAGCAGGGCCUUCGGAUCCCCCUACCUGGCCUGCUACUCUCUAAGCGUCACCAUCCUGCUCCUGAACUUCCUGCGCUCGCACUGCUUCACGCAGGCCAUGCUGAGCCAGCCCAGGAUGGAGAGCCUGGACACCCCCGCGGCCUACAGCCUGGGCCUCGCGCUCCUGGGACUGGGCGUCGUGCUCGUGCUCUCCAGCUUCUUUGCACUGGGGUUCGCUGGAACUUUCCUAGGUGAUUACUUCGGGAUCCUCAAGGAGGCGAGAGUGACCGUGUUCCCCUUCAACAUCCUGGACAACCCCAUGUACUGGGGAAGCACAGCCAACUACCUGGGCUGGGCCAUCAUGCACGCCAGCCCCACGGGCCUGCUCCUGACGGUGCUGGUGGCCCUCACCUACAUAGUGGCUCUCCUAUACGAAGAGCCCUUCACCGCUGAGAUCUACCGGCAGAAAGCCUCCGGGUCCCACAAGAGGAGCUGAUUGAGCUGCAACAGCUUUGCUGAAGGCCUGGCCAGCCUCCUGGCCUGCCCCAAGUGGCAGGCCCUGCGCAGGGCGAGAAUGGUGCCUGCUGCUCAGGGCUCGCCCCCGGCGUGGGCUGCCCCAGUGCCUUGGAACCUGCUGCCUUGGGGACCCUGGACGUGCCGACAUAUGGCCAUUGAGCUCCAACCCACACAUUCCCAUUCACCAAUAAAGGCACCCUGACCCCAA